GAGCACCCUCUGCAUCGUCGCCAUCCCCAGCAAGGGGAGGUGGAGGCAGGGGAAAGUCUGGGGUAGGAAGGAGAAAGACGUCGGCCGGGGUCCCUCUACCCCUCACCCAAGCUCCCCUCAGUUAACCGCUCUAACCCCUAACCCAAGAACUCUCUCAGGGGUCCCAGAGCGUGUGGGGAAGCAAAGGAGGGGCGCAGGGCGCCCUGGGAGUACCAGGUCAGGAAAGGCCGGGCGCACUGCCGAGGAGUGGUGCAGCUCCCGUUACACUUCGGAAAACGGACCCGGAGGGGAAGAUUCGUGCCCCACAUUCCCGACUCCCACUCCCAGGCGGGGGACUUGGAACGGUCCCAGGAGCCCUGGCUCCCAGCCACGAGCUCCACGAUGAGGUAA